GUAGAGACCGGGUCUCACUACAUUGCUCAAGCUGUCUUGAAGUCCUGGCCUCAAGUGGUCCUCCCGCCUUAGACUCCCAAACUGUUGGGAUUACAGGCAUGAGCCACCACAUGCAGCUCAAGACACCAGUUGUUUUUUUCUUCUUCUUUUAUUCUAUUUUUUUGUUUUUAUUUUUGAGACACCAUUUUAAAAAUGCUUUUAAUACACUGUUUUCAAAUUUUUUUGAGACAUAUUCUUGCUAUGUCACCCAGAAUGUUGGGUGGAAUGUUGACUCCUGCAUCUUAUUGUUAUACCAAUUCCAGGCUGGAGCGCAGUGGUGCGAUCAAGGCUGACUGCAACCUCCGUCUCUUGGGCUCAAUUGAUCUUCCUACCUCAGCCUCCUUAGUAGCUGGGACUGCAGGUGCAUGCCAUCAUGCCUGGCUAAUUAUUUAUUUUUUUUGUAGAGAUGGGGUUUUGCCAUGUUGCUCAGGCUGGUCUCAAACUCCUGGGCUCAAGUGAUCCUCCUGCCUCGGCCUCCCGAAGUGCUGGGAUUACAGGUGUGAGCCUCCGCACCCAGUCAAUACACUUUAAUCCAAGUCAGUGUCUAUUUAAAUUUUAAGUUAGUUUAACUCUGAGCCAUGGGCCUGUACCUUGGAAAUAUGUAAUUUAGAGUCAUAAGUAACAGUUAUCUAGCUGAGAGUCAUAUGUGGGUUAUACCAAAUGUACUGCCAUCAUGUGAUUAUAGGUUAGUAGUGUAAUUUUUGGAAUUGGCAGGUCACAGAUGAGAUUGCCAUGGCUUGGUGGAAAGCUCUCCCAACUGUCUUCUCCAGACAGAUAGGUAGAACCUGGAACCAGUGCUAGGACGUGUGUGUAUGUAGGAGGUAGUCAUUGGUUAUAUGAACUUAAAGUUGCUAUCUUAACUUCUGGGCCUUGAAGGAAGGCCAUAUUAGUGACAUCUGCUUAGUUCUUUAUAGUAAACUUGUUAACGCUUGUGCCACAGUCAAGAACCAGAACUGGAAUGUUGACUCCUGCAUCAUCUUACACCAGUUCCAGUAGGAAUUUUGUUAUACAGUUUCUGCUGGAGAUGGCAGUGGGAUUUUUUUUCUUUUUUUUCCUCAUAUGUGAAGUAAUAGUCUGUUCACAACAGAAGAAGCCACAAAACUAAACUUAUUGGUCACUGAAUUUUCUUCAAGGUUACAUACCUCUUGGGUAUUUUAAAUCUAGAUUAUGUUCAUUUUUAUAUUUUUGUUCUCAUUUUUCUAUUUCUUUGUUUUCUUUACUGUGAAUGUGCUCCAGGAUUUUGUACAGAGCUUCUAGUUUCUGUCUGUAAUUUAAAUAUUGAAUUUGUUCUCGAUAAAAGAGAACUUUUUAGCAUAAAGAGAAAGCUAAAAACAUAGAUUAUAGGCCCCAUAAUGAAAUGUGUAGUAGUUGCAUAUGGCUAGUGCUUCUCUGUGUAUUGGAAUUGUACUGUUUUCCCUUAGAAUUUGUUUUUUCUUUAAUGAGUAAUUUUCAGUUAUAUAAAGAAUGUUUGCAUACUUUUAUAAUAAUGAGAACUGUAAUAGCUCAUUUUCCACUCAGCAGAUGAUUUUGGAGAUUUACUAGGUAGAUGUUGAUACAUACAGACCUAGUUUGGGUCAUUGUUCUUUAAAUAAUCAUCCUGUAAACACAUUUAUUUACAGUGUUUUGUCACUUAUUGAAAGUGGGGUUUUUUUUGGCGGGGCGCGCUGAGUCACAUCUGUAAUCCUAGCACUUAGGGAGGCUGAGGCAGGAGAAUCGCUUGAACCCAGGAGGCAGAGGUUGCGGUCAGCCGAGAUCGUGCCAUUGUACUCCAGCCUGGGCAAAAGAGCAAAACUUUGUCUCAAAAAAAGAAAAAAAAAAGGAAUGCUGCAAGGUCUCUGGGAGUCAAACUAUUUUGAUGGCUAUUUUGACUCUGGUAUGGUAUGAAAAGGAAAACUAGAAAAGAGGAGGAAAAAACAAUAAAUAUGCAAGAAGAAAUAAAUACAUUGCAAAACAGAAGAAUGGGAAAUAAUCAAGAGUUGGAAAAUUAGGAAACAAAAGGCAAAAUGAAGGAGAGUACAUCGGAUAUAACAAAAGGGACCACUUAAUAGUGAGUCUUCCAACCAGAGCUUGUGCAGCGUCGGAUCCUUGAGUGAUAAAGAAGUAGAGACUCCCGAGAAAAAGCAGAAUGACCAGCGAAAUCGGAAAAGAAAAGCUGAACCAUAUGAAACUAGCCAAGCGACGAGUAGAACAGCCCCUCUAUGGUUUAGAUGGCAGUGCUGCAAAGGAGGCAACGGAGGAGCAGUCUGCUCUGCCAACCCUCAUGUCAGUGAUGCUAGCAAAACCUCGGCUUGACACAGAGCAGCUGGCGCAAAGGGGAGCUGGCCUCUGCUUCACUUUUGUUUCAGCUCAGCAAAACAGUCCCUCAUCUACGGGAUCUGGCAACACAGAGCAUUCCUGCAGCUCCCAAAAACAGAUCUCCAUCCAGCACAGACAGACCCAGUCCGACCUCACAAUAGAAAAAAUAUCUGCACUAGAAAACAGUAAGAAUUCUGACUUAGAGAAGAAGGAGGGAAGAAUAGAUGAUUUAUUAAGAGCCAACUGUGAUUUGAGACGGCAGAUUGAUGAACAGCAAAAGAUGCUAGAGAAAUACAAGGAACGAUUAAAUAGAUGUGUGACAAUGAGCAAGAAACUCCUUAUAGAAAAGUCAAAACAAGAGAAGAUGGCGUGUAGAGAUAAGAGCAUGCAAGACCGCUUGAGACUGGGCCACUUUACUACUGUCCGACACGGAGCCUCAUUUACUGAACAGUGGACAGAUGGUUAUGCUUUUCAGAAUCUUAUCAAGCAACAGGAAAGGAUAAAUUCACAGAGGGAAGAGAUAGAAAGACAACGGAAAAUGUUAGCAAAGCGGAAACCUCCUGCCAUGGGUCAGGCCCCUCCUGCAACCAAUGAGCAGAAACAGCGGAAAAGCAAGACCAAUGGAGCUGAAAAUGAAACGCCCUCUUCUGGGAAUACAGAGCUAAAGGAUACAGCCCCAGCCUUAGGAGCCCACAGUUUACUUAGGUUAACGUUAGCAGAAUACCAUGAACAAGAAGAAAUCUUCAAACUCAGAUUAGGUCAUCUUAAAAAGGAGGAAGCAGAGAUCCAGGCAGAGCUGGAGAGACUAGAAAGGGUUAGAAAUCUACAUAUCAGGGAACUAAAAAGGAUACAUAAUGAAGAUAAUUCACAAUUUAAAGAUCAUCCAACGCUAAAUGACAGAUAUUUGUUGUUACAUCUUUUGGGUAGAGGAGGUUUCAGUGAAGUUUACAAGGCAUUUGAUCUAACAGAGCAAAGAUACGUAGCUGUGAAAAUUCACCAGUUAAAUAAAAACUGGAGAGAUGAGAAAAAGGAGAAUUACCACAAGCAUGCAUGUAGGGAAUACCGGAUUCAUAAAGAGCUGGAUCAUCCCAGAAUAGUUAAGCUGUAUGAUUACUUUUCACUGGAUACUGACUCGUUUUGUACAGUAUUAGAAUACUGUGAGGGAAAUGAUCUGGACUUCUACCUGAAACAGCACAAAUUAAUGUCGGAGAAAGAGGCCCGGUCCAUUAUCAUGCAGAUUGUGAAUGCUUUAAAGUACUUAAAUGAAAUAAAACCUCCCAUCAUACACUAUGACCUCAAACCAGGUAAUAUUCUUUUAGUAAAUGGUACAGCGUGUGGAGAGAUAAAAAUUACAGAUUUUGGUCUUUCGAAGAUCAUGGAUGAUGAUAGCUACAAUUCAGUGGAUGGCAUGGAGCUAACAUCACAAGGUGCUGGUACUUAUUGGUAUUUACCACCAGAGUGUUUUGUGGUUGGGAAAGAACCACCAAAGAUCUCAAAUAAAGUUGAUGUGUGGUCGGUGGGUGUGAUCUUCUAUCAGUGUCUUUAUGGAAGGAAGCCUUUUGGCCAUAACCAGUCUCAGCAAGACAUCCUACAAGAGAAUACGAUUCUUAAAGCUACUGAAGUGCAGUUCCCGCCAAAGCCAGUAGUAACACCUGAAGCAAAGGCGUUUAUUCGACGAUGCUUGGCCUACCGAAAGGAGGACCGCAUUGAUGUCCAGCAGCUGGCCUGUGAUCCCUACUUGUUGCCUCACAUCCGAAAGUCAGUCUCUACAAGUAGCCCUGCUGGAGCUGCUAUUGCAUCAACCUCUGGGGCGUCCAAUAACAGUUCUUCUAAUUGAGACUGACUCCAAGGCCACAAACUGUUCAACACACACAAAGUGGACAAAUGGCGUUCAGCAGCGGGUUUGGAACAUAGCGAAUCCGAAUGGAUCUGAUGAAACCUGUACCAGGUGCUUUUAUUUUCUUGCUUUUUUCCCAUCCAUAGAGCAUGACAGCAUCGAUUCUCAUUGAGGAGAAACCUUGGGCAGCUCCGGCCAGGCCUUGUAGGAAAAGGCCCCGCCCGAGGUUCCAGCGUCAACGGCCACUGUGUGUGGCUGCUCUGAGUGAGGAAAAAAUUAAAAAGAAAAACUGGUUCCAUGUACUGUGAACUUGAAAACUUGCAGACUCAGGGGGGUCCCUGAUGCAGUGCUUCAGAUGAAGAAUGUGGACUUGAAAAUACAGACUGGGCUAGUCCAGUGUCUAUAUUUAAACUUGUUCUUUUCUUUUAAUAAAGUUUAGGUAACAUCUCCUGAAAAGCUUGUAGCACAAAGGCUCAGCUGGGGAUGGUGUUUGACUUCGGAGGAAAAAAGUUGCUAUUGCCCGUUAAAGGCACUAGAGUUAGUGUUUUAUCCCUAAAUAAUUUCAAUUUUUAAAAACAUGCAGCUUCCCUCUCCCCUUUUUUAUUUUUGAAAGAAUACAUUUGGUCAUAAAGUGAAACCCGUAUUAGCAAGUACGUGGCAAUGUUCAUUCCAAUCAGAUGCAGCUUUCUCCUCCGUCUGGUCUCCUGUUUGCAAUUGCUUCCCUCAUCUCAGUAGGGAAAAAAUUGAGUGGGAGUACUGAGAUGUGUGGGUUUUUGCCAUUGGACAAAGAAUGAGGUUAGAAGACUGCAGCUUGGAGUCUCUCUAGGUUUUCAACUAUUUCUUCACAAUUUGAACACUUGACGGUUGUCCCUUUUAAUUUAUUUGAAGUGCUAUUUUUUUAAAUAAAGGUUCAUCUGUCCAUGCAGUCCUCUUGGAUUCUCUGAAUGUAGUAACUAUGAAGCUAUGCCAAAGGUAGGCAGAAAAUGGGCUUGGGAGCCAGACACUCCAGGGAUCAGUAGUUCCUACCCAUAGUCUUUGUGUGCUUGCUAAAUGGUGUACAUUUCUUGUUAACCACGUUAUUAAAACUUGAUCAGCACAUAAGCUUUCUUCUGUUAGAUCUUUUGGCAGCAAACAACCUUCCCCCCAAGCCUCUGAAUUUUGUGGGUGUGUGGUGGUGUGUGUCUGUGUGUGCAUGUACACACACACUUUGUCUAGCUCACUUUAAAAGAUUCAUCAAAUGGAAUUUUAAAAAUAAUCUGAAAAGAAAUAGAUAUUUCAGGCCGGGCCUGGUGGUUCACGCCUGUAAUCCCAGCACUUUGGGAGGCCGAGGUGGGUGGAUCACGAGGUCGGGAGUUCGAGAUCAGUCUGGUCAACAUGGUGAAACGCCAUCUCUACUAAAAAUAUAAAAAUUAGCCUGGCGUGGUGGCGUGUGCCUCUAGUCCCAGCUACCCGGGAGGCUGAGGCAGGAGAAUUUCUGGAACCCAGGAGGCGGAGGUUGCAGUGAGCCGAGAUGGCACCACUGCAAUCCAGCCUAGGCAACAGAAUGAGACUCUGUCUCAGAAAAAAAAAAAAAAAAAAAAGGAGAAAUAGAUGUUUCAAAUAUGAACAUUCUUUUGGCACCAAUUUUCUUUUUUAAUUUGGUUGUUUCUGAGAUGUAUGAUCAACUGAAGAUGGAGCUGAAAUGGGAGACGGGUGGCCCCACCGUGCCCUUGAAACAGCAGAGCACUCCUCAGUAGAGAGGGAGGGAGCCAAGAGCCUGAACAUGUGGUCGCCAGCUUGGAAUGUUACUGACAUAUGUGGCGAGGGCUUAGCCAGAAAUAUUUAAAGAUGUAGUAUUCCGGCCUGUGAGUUGUCUGGGCAGGGAGGGGGAGUCAGAAAGGGUAGAGAGCUCUCAAAUAACUCAUGACUCUAGUGUUCCUUUCACAUGUGAACAGUGUCACUGAUGACACAUUUUCUAGGACCUUCGUUUGUUUUGUGGACCUGCCUCAGUCUCCUCAGUAUCAGGCGAUCUUAAGGGAAGAUGGAGUGUUUCAAAUUGGAGAGAAGUUCAUGGGUAGGUAUCGUCCUGUGGAAUUCUGAAUGCAAGGAAGUCAACCCCAGAGGCCUUGGUACCCCCAGCUUUCUAAAACUACUUUAUUACAAUUUAUAUGUAUAUACACAUGCACAUAUAAACGUGUGCAUUUAUGUAUGUGUGUAUAGUACCUUUUUUAAAAAAACAUUUCCUCCAAGCUGCUAAGCAAAGGGUCUCACAGGUCGAGCACAGUGCUGAGAGGAUGGUGUCUGCAUAAUGAAGACAUGGAUGAAGCUGAGACCGUGUUCAAACUCACUGAAAACAAUGAAGUUCUAUUCCUUUUUUCUUCCUCUCCAAUGAUCUUGCAGUUGAUUUGUUUGUUUUUUAAUUUUUUAACAUUUUUUUAACGUUGAAAAAAUGCUGCGUCUUUCUUUAAGCCUUCCCAGUAACUUCCUGCCUUUUUUUUCCCCGUGGGCUUUUAAGUGAAGCUGCAGGAUUUUAUCUUUCAAUCUGCCCUUUCUACCCUUGUCCUAUUGAAAGGAUGCCCUCUUCCCUUGCUUUUUUGGUCUAGGGCCUGUUUGGAGCUAACUAGGCUUGGCUGAGUCCGGGCAAGACCUUCUUCCGAGGCAUGGACAAGCCCCAGAGAACAUGCAGAACAUUGACCUUUCCAUUGACUGUCUUUCAAGCAGCCAGUGAAAUCACUAAGUGGGGUUCUUCCAUGACAUAUUUUGUUAAUAUGGGUUUCACUUUUUCCAAGAAUAGUCCCUUGUUGCCACAAUGUUGAUUUACUUUACACAAUGACAGUAUGUAUUAAUUUGUAAUUAAACCCAUCCAGAUUGUUUUAGCCUUUUCCCAAUGGGGUGGGGGAGGGAAGAAGGAUAUUAAAAUAAGUUUUAAGAAGCAAA